GGGGUUGUUAUCUCUCAGGGCUUAGCACUUGUUGGGGAUGGGUGAAGUCCAGUCCCGAGUCACAGUGUGUGUUGUGGGAGGUUGCUGAUAUUCAUAGCCCUGUAUGUUUGAGUAAUGACAAUAUCCACCUCCACCUUCAGGGUGAGGAGCUGUUGGCCUAUCUGUGUCUGUCUGUCUGUCUGUCUGUCAUCUGCACCUGUCUCUCCGAGGGAAAGAAGGCAGGCCCCAGGGUCUUUCCCCAGGAUGGCCUUGGGUGAGCUCCUGCUGUCCUCUCUGCCCAGGAAAUGAAGGCCCUUUGAGGUCAGGUGGAUGAGGAUGUCAGUGUGAAGAUGGACACUGUGCCUGGAGUGAACCUGAGCUGGAUCCUGAAUGAGAUGCAUGACCAGGACAAGAAAUUGGUGGAGAAGAGCUACAAGGAUGCCAAGGGCUGUUUCUUCAGCAUGAGAGAGGGGCUGAACUGCGAGGUGGCCACCAACACAGAGGCCCUGCAGAGCGGCAGGAUAGAGAUAUGGAGCUCUACAUCUCUGUGCAGAACCUGAGCCAUCCCAGCUCAGCAAGGUAGGGCCUCUGUCCCCUCCCCACCCUGUACCUAUCACCCCAGGGUGAGCCCAGCCUUAUAGACCCCUGCUUGGAGGUGUGUUACGGGACCCAACUGGCCCAGCUGCAGGGGCUCAUCAGAAGCAUGGAGCAGCAGCUGUGCGAGCUCUGCUGCGACGCGGAGCACCAGGACCAUGAGCACCAGGUCCUUCUGGACGUGAAGACACGGCUGGAGCAGGAGAUCGCCACCUACAGCCGCUUGCUAGAGGUUGAGGACGCUCAAGUCACAGGGAGAAGACGUCCACCCACACAUCAGGAGACAGGCCUGGAACAGAGCCUUCCUGCACAGCCUCAGAAGGGACCCACCCUGGUGACACCUUGAUCUUGGACUGACACUCAUGACCUCCAGUACUGUGAGACAGUAACAUUCUGUUGUUGAAGGUGCCCAGUCUGUGGUACUGUAAAACAGCCCUGGGAAACUAACGCAGCCUGUUAGCCCACAGAUGGUGAAGGGAUGGAAUGCUCCACGGAGCUCCAGGCUUACUAUCUACAGCCCCCAAAGUGUGCUGCGGGACCCUUGGGUGGGUGUAGGUAUGCAAGGUAAUUUUGGGUGGUUCAAGGUGAAUAAUUUCAAUUGACAUAAUAAUGUAUUUAUCUUGCUGGGUAAAUGAGGGAUACCCAACUGUUAGGAACCAGGCAACACAGCAGGAGGUGAGCAGCCAGCCAGUGAGCAAAGCUUCAUCUGUAGAAACAGCCACUUCCCAUCCCUCGCAUUACCGCAUGAGCUCUGCCUCCUGUCAGAUGAGCGGUGCCGUUAGAUUCUCACAGAAGCAUGAACCCUACUGUGAACUGCGCAUGCCAGGGAUCUAGAUUGCGUGCUCCUUAUGAGAACCUAAUGCCUGAUGAUCUGUGACUGUCUCAUCACUGCCAGAUGGAACCACGUAGUUGCAGGAAAACAAGUUCAGGGCUCCCACUGAUUCUACAUUAUGGGCUGUCAUUGGGACAGUCUGAGAUGGGGAGUCGGGGGAGACAAUGGAUGAAUGGAUGGAUGAAUGGACAGCAGUCCAGGGAGAUGUCCCUGUGUGUCCUGAACUGGGCCCUUCCUCCAGUGAGAAGCCUUCCUGAGCUGACUUGGGGACAGUGGCUAUGGUAUGGGCGGUGUUGGCCUCUGGGCAGCUACAGAGGAGGGUCAUCCCUGAGCACUCACCGGGCGCCCGUUCUACACUGCCCAUGUAGACGAUUUUCUCUUUCGUCUUCAUGGUGGCUUCGUAGAGUGGGUGCUGUUCCCGAAUGUACCCAUUCGACAGGUGAGCCGUCUGGGGUCAGAGAGGCAGUAACUGGCCUGGGAAUCCAGACAAGACCCUGGGUUUUGCUCUCAGCCCUGCUGUGUGCCAUGCUAGACUUCAGGCCUCAACCCUGAGACCUCCCUGCUCUAGAUCCCAAAUCUGCCCAGAUUUCCGAUCCCAAUGGGGCAGAGCCUGGCCCUGGCAGAGACACUGGGAUGGAUCCACUGUGGGUGGGGAGGAGGGAAGGGUCCUCAGAACACACCUGGGGCCUAAGCUGGGUCUUGAUGGUCACUGUGGGACCCACUGGACACACACAGUCCCUUGUCUGGGAGUGGCAUGGGGAGCCUUCUGCCCUUGGGCAGUUGUGGAAAGUGAAGGAGCCCUGGAGAGCUGGCUGAGGGGAGACUAUCUUCCCUUGUGUUCAAAGGGGUCCAGGCACUGGGGCUCUCCCCAAGUAUUUCUUAUUCUGUCUGGCCUCGCUUUCCUUUUGCCCUGAGUAUUCUCAGGAGGGACGGUCCAUCUAGAUGUCCUCCAGGAGCAAGGACCCACUGUUCUUCAUCAGUGACCCAGGAAAAUGAAGCCCCCUCCUGUGGGGACAGCUCAGAAUGGUGGAGUCCACAGUCCCUCCCUGAGAGACAUGGUUUCCAUGAGCACAGUGGCUGCUUUGGAGACAGUAAUCAUUUUCAUCCCCAAAACCAAACACACUCCUGCUCAAAUGGUGUUAUUGCUAAAGCAGCUUCACUGGUUAGACUGAAGGGCCAUGGUAGCCCAAGUGAUGAGCGGGGUAGAAUGGAGCAGUCAGGAGAGAUCUUGUUCCCCGUAGGAAACUGGGCAUCUCUGUGGCCCUGAACAUCCCAGGAGGCCGAUCGUACAGAGACCUCUGGUGCCUGACCGCAGUUCACAUCCACAUCCCUGGAAUAGACCAUCACAGGCUCUUCACCCUUGGCAGGUGGACACCAUUCAACCUGCCGGGGCAGGAUGGACAUGGUAGAGAAUGCAGAUAGUUUGCAGGCACAGGAGCGGAAGGACAUACUUAUGAAGUAUGACAAGGGACACCGAGCUGGGCUGCCAGAGGACAAGGGGCCUGAGCCCGUUGGAAUCAACAGCAGCAUUGAUCGUUUUGGCAUUUUGCAUGAGACGGAGCUGCCUCCUGUGACUGCACGGGAGGCGAAGAAAAUUCGGCGGGAGAUGACACGAACGAGCAAGUGGAUGGAAAUGCUGGGAGAAUGGGAGACAUAUAAGCACAGUAGCAAACUCAUAGAUCGAGUGUACAAGGGAAUUCCCAUGAACAUCCGGGGCCCGGUGUGGUCAGUCCUCCUGAACAUUCAGGAAAUCAAGUUGAAAAACCCCGGAAGAUACCAGAUCAUGAAGGAGAGGGGCAAGAGGUCAUCUGAACACAUCCACCACAUCGACCUGGACGUGAGGACGACUCUCCGGAACCAUGUCUUCUUUAGGGAUCGAUAUGGAGCCAAGCAGAGGGAACUAUUCUACAUCCUCCUGGCCUAUUCGGAGUAUAACCCGGAGGUGGGCUACUGCAGGGACCUGAGCCACAUCACCGCCUUGUUCCUCCUUUAUCUGCCUGAGGAGGACGCAUUCUGGGCACUGGUGCAGCUGCUGGCCAGUGAGAGGCACUCCCUGCCAGGAUUCCACAGCCCAAAUGGUGGGACAGUCCAGGGGCUCCAAGACCAACAGGAGCAUGUGGUACCCAAGUCACAACCCAAGACCAUGUGGCAUCAGGACAAGGAAGGUCUAUGCGGGCAGUGUGCCUCGUUAGGCUGCCUUCUCCGGAACCUGAUUGACGGGAUCUCUCUCGGGCUCACCCUGCGCCUGUGGGACGUGUAUUUGGUGGAAGGAGAACAGGUGUUGAUGCCAAUAACCAGCAUUGCUCUUAAGGUUCAGCAGAAGCGCCUCAUGAAGACAUCCAGGUGUGGCCUGUGGGCACGUCUGCGGAACCAAUUCUUCGAUACCUGGGCCAUGAACGAUGACACCGUGCUCAAGCAUCUUAGGGCCUCUACGAAGAAACUAACAAGGAAGCAAGGGGACCUGCCACCCCCAGCCAAACGCGAGCAAGGGUCCUUGGCACCCAGGCCUGUGCCGGCUUCACGUGGUGGGAAGACCCUCUGCAAGGGGUAUAGGCAGGCCCCUCCAGGCCCACCAGCCCAGUUCCAGCGGCCCAUUUGCUCAGCUUCCCCGCCAUGGGCAUCUCGUUUUUCCACGCCCUGUCCUGGUGGGGCUGUCCGGGAAGACACGUACCCUGUGGGCACUCAGGGUGUGCCCAGCCUGGCCCUGGCUCAGGGAGGACCUCAGGGUUCCUGGAGAUUCCUGGAGUGGAAGUCAAUGCCCCGGCUCCCAACGGACCUGGAUAUAGGGGGCCCUUGGUUCCCCCAUUAUGAUUUUGAAUGGAGCUGCUGGGUCCGUGCCAUAUCCCAGGAGGACCAGCUGGCCACCUGCUGGCAGGCUGAACACUGCGGAGAGGUUCACAACAAAGAUAUGAGUUGGCCUGAGGAGAUGUCUUUUACAGCAAAUAGUAGUAAAAUAGAUAGACAAAAGGUUCCCACAGAAAAGGGAGCCACAGGUCUAAGCAACCUGGGAAACACAUGCUUCAUGAACUCAAGCAUCCAGUGCGUUAGUAACACACAGCCACUGACACAGUAUUUUAUCUCAGGGAGACAUCUUUAUGAACUCAACAGGACAAAUCCCAUUGGUAUGAAGGGGCAUAUGGCUAAAUGCUAUGGUGAUUUAGUGCAGGAACUCUGGAGUGGAACUCAGAAGAGUGUUGCCCCAUUAAAGCUUCGGCGGACCAUAGCAAAAUAUGCUCCCAAGUUUGAUGGGUUUCAGCAACAAGACUCCCAAGAACUUCUGGCUUUUCUCUUGGAUGGUCUUCAUGAAGAUCUCAACCGAGUCCAUGAAAAGCCAUAUGUGGAACUGAAGGACAGUGAUGGCCGACCAGACUGGGAAGUAGCUGCAGAGGCCUGGGACAACCAUCUAAGAAGAAAUAGAUCAAUUAUUGUGGAUUUGUUCCAUGGGCAGCUAAGAUCUCAAGUCAAAUGCAAGACAUGUGGGCAUAUAAGUGUCCGAUUUGACCCUUUCAAUUUUUUGUCUUUGCCACUACCAAUGGACAGUUACAUGGACUUAGAAAUAACAGUGAUUAAGUUAGAUGGUACUACCCCUGUACGGUAUGGACUAAGACUGAAUAUGGAUGAAAAGUACACAGGUUUAAAAAAACAGCUGAGGGAUCUCUGUGGACUUAAUUCAGAACAAAUCCUACUAGCAGAAGUACAUGAUUCCAACAUAAAGAACUUUCCUCAGGAUAACCAAAAAGUACAACUCUCAGUGAGCGGAUUUUUGUGUGCAUUUGAAAUUCCUGUCCCUUCAUCUCCAAUUUCAGCUUCUAGUCCAACACAAAUAGAUUUCUCCUCUUCACCAUCUACAAAUGGAAUGUUCACCCUAACUACCAAUGGGGACCUACCCAAACCAAUAUUCAUCCCCAAUGGAAUGCCAAACACUGUUGUGCCAUGUGGAACUGAGAAGAACUUCACAAAUGGAAUGGUUAAUGGUCACAUGCCAUCUCUUCCUGACAGCCCCUUUACAGGUUACAUCAUUGCAGUCCACCGAAAAAUGAUGAGGACAGAACUGUAUUUCCUGUCACCUCAGGAGAAUCGCCCCAGCCUCUUUGGAAUGCCAUUGAUUGUUCCAUGCACUGUGCAUACCCGGAAGAAAGACCUAUAUGAUGCGGUUUGGAUUCAAGUAUCCUGGUUAGCAAGACCACUCCCACCUCAGGAAGCUAGUAUUCAUGCCCAGGAUCGUGAUAACUGUAUGGGCUAUCAAUAUCCAUUCACUCUACGAGUUGUGCAGAAAGAUGGGAACUCCUGUGCUUGGUGCCCACAGUAUAGAUUUUGCAGAGGCUGUAAAAUUGAUUGUGGGGAAGACAGAGCUUUCAUUGGAAAUGCCUAUAUUGCUGUGGAUUGGCACCCCACAGCCCUUCACCUUCGCUAUCAAACAUCCCAGGAAAGGGUUGUAGAUAAGCAUGAGAGUGUGGAGCAGAGUCGGCGAGCGCAAGCCGAGCCCAUCAACCUGGACAGCUGUCUCCGUGCUUUCACCAGUGAGGAAGAGCUAGGGGAAAGUGAGAUGUACUACUGUUCCAAGUGUAAGACCCACUGCUUAGCAACAAAGAAGCUGGAUCUCUGGAGGCUUCCACCCUUCCUGAUUAUUCACCUUAAGCGAUUUCAAUUUGUAAAUGAUCAGUGGAUAAAAUCACAGAAAAUUGUCAGAUUUCUUCGGGAAAGUUUUGAUCCGAGUGCUUUUUUGGUACCACGAGACCCGGCCCUCUGCCAGCAUAAACCACUCACACCCCAGGGGGAUGAGCUCUCCAAGCCCAGGAUUCUGGCAAGAGAGGUGAAGAAAGUGGAUGCGCAGAGUUCGGCUGGAAAAGAGGACAUGCUCCUAAGCAAAAGCCCAUCCUCACUCAGCGCUAACAUCAGCAGCAGCCCAAAAGGUUCUCCUUCUUCAUCAAGAAAAAGUGGAACCAGCUGUCCCUCCAGCAAAAACAGCAGCCCUAAUAGCAGCCCACGGACUUUGGGGAGGAGCAAAGGGAGGCUCCGGCUGCCCCAGAUUGGCAGCAAAAAUAAGCCGUCAAGUAGUAAGAAGAACUUGGAUGCCAGCAAAGAGAAUGGGGCUGGGCAGAUCUGUGAGCUGGCUGACGCCUUGAGCCGAGGGCAUAUGCGGGGGGGCAGCCAACCAGAGCUGGUCACUCCUCAGGACCAUGAGGUAGCUUUGGCCAAUGGAUUCCUUUAUGAGCAUGAAGCAUGUGGCAAUGGCUGUGGCGAUGGCUACAGCAAUGGUCAGCUUGGAAACCACAGUGAAGAAGACAGCACUGAUGACCAAAGAGAAGACACUCAUAUUAAGCCUAUUUAUAAUCUAUAUGCAAUUUCAUGCCAUUCAGGAAUUCUGAGUGGGGGCCAUUACAUCACUUAUGCCAAAAACCCAAACUGCAAGUGGUACUGUUAUAAUGACAGCAGCUGUGAGGAACUUCACCCUGAUGAAAUUGACACCGACUCUGCCUACAUUCUUUUCUAUGAGCAGCAGGGGAUAGACUACGCACAAUUUCUGCCAAAGAUUGAUGGCAAAAAGAUGGCAGACACAAGCAGUACGGAUGAAGACUCUGAGUCUGAUUACGAAAAGUACUCUAUGUUACAGUAAAGCUACCACUCUGGCUGCUAGACAGCUUGGUGGCGAGGGAGAUGACUCCUUGUAGCUGAUACUUGGCAAAAGUGUCACUGAAAGACAAGCUAAAUGUAGUUAUUUUAUCCUGUUAGAACAAAAAUUCUAAUUAAAAUAGUUAACUUGAAGAGUAGAAACAAUUGUAUUUUGAAGUCUCAUACAAGCUGUCUGAUAGAGAACUUUCAGGCAGAUCCCACCAUUAGCCUGUAAACAAAAGGUGUGGCACCAGCCACCUGGGACCAAAUAAGAAUUGAAUUGUGCUUGUCCAGAUAUGAACAAAUAUGUAGUGAGUAUAGAGUUUACCAAUAAUCAUAACAAAUAUUAAAGAUUUCCUUGGAGUCAGAGGAAAAAACAAACAAUUAUAAUGUUGUCUAGGGACGACAUGAUACGCUACCUCCUUUUUCCUGAAGUUUUAUUCCAUUAUAUUGACAAGAUGGAGAAAGCAAGAUCAUGAAGGUGUGCAAAUGAUUCUUACGGCAUGGACAAGGAUUUUUCAAUUUAUUUUUUAAACUGUUUCCAUACCCUUUCUUUUUCUUGCUUUUUGUUUUUGCCAUUGUGUUUACGUUUGAGACACAACCAGUCAUUGGUGGCAGGGGCAUAGAGUGGUCAGUCUGAAAGGGAGGCUCUCUUAAGAGCUAUGUGCCUUCCAACCAGAGGGAGACCCAGUAGAAAGAAAAACAUCCUGGGAAAUCCAGCUACCAGGGCCCUCCCAGUGGAGGCAUCUUACAUUUAGGCUACUUCAAGUAUCCUCAGAAAUGUAUUCUGCACCCCCGGCCCCGCCCAUGCUGAGGGAAGGGGAGCAGUUGCCAAUAUUUGCACCAUCUUCACAUGCACAUGUUGCAACAAGAGCUUCUGGGAAGGUAAGCGGCAUCGGAGCUAGAUCACGUUUCACAAUUAGUGGUUAUUCUUUUCUGUGUUUGUUUUGCACUUUAAAAAAGAGAGAACACAUGCAAAUGAACUUGCUUGUGUGUAUUUGAUGGCUCUAAGGGCUAUAAAUUACAAACAAAACACAUCCCAGACAUUAGGAGUUCAUAAGUAUAUUUAAUGAAAUUGGUGGUUUUAGGAAGUCAACUUUAGUUUUGCUUUGUUUGCAUGUCCACUGGUUUUUUUAUUUUGAUAUUUGUCUUUUUUUAAAUUUUACAGUAGUCAUUGAAAGUUAUGUUUCUUUGCUUACUUCAUUUUUUCCCUCUAAUUAUUUAAGAUUGGAACAAAAGUAUAAAUAUUAUUUAUUUGAGGUAGAAUUUUUUUCAUGUAGUUUCUUAAUAUAUACUUGAAGGAAAUGUUUCACCUUAUUUUUGGUCUUUGUUUAUUCAUUUAGACCCUGCAAGUUGAUUCUCAUUGCCAGAUUCCAUUACCCUUUCUUCCUCAUAGGUAGUAAUUACCAAUGUAACUAAGCAUUUGUGUUCUGAUAUCUGAGGCCAGUAACUAUUAAUAUCUAGUUCUCAGAGCAUUUGGAAAGGUUAUCUUAAAUGGCUACCUAAAUUGAAAUCCUUUUCAGAAAAAAUAUAAUUGCAAGUAGGUAGGAGUGGCCUAAAUUGUCUAAUGUAAUAAAGUCAGACAAAAUGCACACUUUAUAGUUUCAAGAUUUUCAGUAAAUAAAAUCUGUCCAUUCCUACCUGGACAUGUCCCAUUAAAAAGUGGAAGAUUUUAAAUAAUUUCUUUACAGAUGUUUUAUUUAAACAGGUAGCACAAUCUACUAAUGUUGUGUGAUUUGUGUUAUACUGGUUGUAAUUAAUUUUUUUAAUUCAUGAACUAGCGGAAAAUUUAUUAAAUUAACUAUUAACUACAUUCACCUUGUAAAUUACUGUAUAAAACUUGUUGACAAUGCACUGACUUUAGAAAGAUGUUAAUGUACAUAAAUAGAGUGUAAAUAAAAUAGUGUUGAUGUACUGAAAUAUGAACUGUAUCAAAAGUAUUGGUAAUUGUAUAUGGGGUGUACCUGUUUAUCUGUUAACUAUUAUCCAAACAAAUUAAAUACUGUGGUUGCCUCUA